GCGGUACUAGCGGUGCCCGCCGAAGGGGGAGGAGGCGAGGAGCGAGCCGUGCGGCCAGAGCGGGAAAGAGACUCGUCUUUGCGUCCGAGUUCUGGAGCCGCCGCACCCCGACUCCUGGGGCCGCGGCAGCGGCUGCGAGGGGACGGGCGUCCGCUGUCUCCUGGGUUCCCCUCGUAGCGACCCGCGGGAUCGGAAAAAAAGGAGAAGAUGGAGGAGGAGGGUGGCAGCAGCGGCGGCGCCGCGGGGACCAGCGCGGACGGCGGCGACGGAGGAGAGCAGCUCCUCACUGUCAAGCACGAGCUGCGGACUGCUAAUUUGACAGGACAUGCUGAGAAGGUGGGAAUAGAAAAUUUUGAGCUCCUGAAGGUCCUAGGAACUGGAGCUUAUGGAAAAGUAUUUCUAGUUCGUAAAAUAAGUGGCCAUGAUACUGGAAAGCUGUAUGCCAUGAAAGUUUUGAAAAAGGCAACAAUCGUUCAAAAGGCCAAAACCACAGAGCAUACAAGGACAGAACGACAAGUCCUGGAACACAUUAGGCAGUCGCCAUUUUUGGUAACAUUACAUUAUGCUUUCCAGACAGAAACCAAACUUCAUCUCAUUUUAGAUUAUAUAAAUGGUGGUGAACUUUUUACUCAUCUUUCUCAAAGAGAGCGUUUCACAGAGCAUGAGGUGCAGAUUUAUGUUGGAGAGAUUGUGCUUGCCCUCGAACAUCUCCACAAGUUGGGGAUUAUAUAUCGUGAUAUUAAGCUUGAGAAUAUUCUACUUGAUUCUAAUGGCCAUGUGGUGCUGACAGAUUUUGGUCUGAGUAAGGAGUUUGUGGCUGAUGAAACUGAAAGAGCAUAUUCCUUUUGUGGAACUAUUGAAUACAUGGCACCAGAUAUUGUCAGAGGGGGAGAUUCAGGACAUGACAAGGCAGUUGACUGGUGGAGUUUGGGUGUUCUAAUGUAUGAAUUACUAACUGGAGCAUCUCCUUUCACUGUUGAUGGAGAAAAAAAUUCCCAAGCUGAGAUAUCUAGAUUUGACAUUAAAAAUUAAAAAUAGAGAUUCCACUUCCAAAGAAGAUGGAAUAAACAGGGACCAGAUUUACUUUCCUGCCUGAAACAAUUUUAACAAUGGGCAAAAUAUAUGAAACAACAGAUUUGAAGACAUUGGACAUCUGGAAGUGAAGGACAGUGUUCUUUGAGAGGCGGAAAAAUAAAUGAGGAGAAUAUUAAAAAGUGAGCCUCCAUAUCCCCAAGAAAUGAGUGCUUUAGCGAAAGACCUAAUUCAGCGUCUUUUGAUGAAAGAUCCCAAGAAGAGAUUGGGAUGUGGUCCACGUGAUGCAGAUGAAAUCAAAGAACAUCUCUUCUUUCAGAAAAUAAAUUGGGAUGAUUUAGCCGCCAAAAAAGUGCCUGCACCAUUUAAGCCAGUCAUUCGAGAUGAAUUAGAUGUGAGUAACUUUGCAGAAGAGUUCACAGAAAUGGAUCCCACUUAUUCUCCCGCAGCCCUGCCCCAGAGUUCUGAGAAGCUGUUUCAGGGCUAUUCCUUUGUUGCUCCUUCCAUCCUAUUCAAGCGUAAUGCAGCUGUCAUAGACCCUCUUCAGUUUCACAUGGGAGUUGAACGUCCUGGAGUGACAAAUGUUGCCAGGAGUGCAAUGAUGAAGGACUCUCCAUUCUAUCAACACUAUGACCUAGAUUUGAAGGACAAACCCCUGGGAGAAGGUAGUUUUUCAAUUUGUCGAAAGUGUGUGCAUAAAAAAAGUAACCAAGCUUUUGCAGUCAAAAUAAUCAGCAAAAGGAUGGAAGCCAAUACUCAAAAGGAAAUAACAGCUCUGAAACUCUGUGAAGGACACCCCAAUAUUGUGAAGUUGCAUGAAGUUUUUCAUGAUCAGCUUCACACGUUUCUAGUGAUGGAACUUCUGAAUGGAGGAGAACUGUUUGAGCGCAUUAAGAAAAAGAAGCACUUCAGUGAGACGGAAGCCAGCUACAUCAUGAGGAAGCUUGUUUCAGCUGUAAGCCACAUGCAUGAUGUUGGAGUGGUGCACAGGGAUCUGAAACCUGAGAAUUUAUUGUUCACCGAUGAAAAUGACAAUUUGGAAAUUAAAAUAAUUGAUUUUGGAUUUGCACGGCUAAAGCCACCGGAUAAUCAGCCCCUGAAGACUCCAUGCUUCACCCUUCAUUAUGCCGCCCCAGAGCUCUUGAAUCAGAACGGCUACGAUGAGUCCUGUGACCUGUGGAGCUUGGGCGUCAUUUUGUACACAAUGUUGUCAGGACAGGUUCCCUUCCAAUCUCAUGACCGAAGUUUGACGUGUACCAGCGCGGUGGAAAUCAUGAAGAAAAUUAAAAAGGGAGAUUUCUCCUUUGAAGGAGAAGCCUGGAAGAAUGUAUCCCAAGAGGCUAAAGAUUUGAUCCAAGGACUUCUCACAGUAGAUCCAAACAAAAGGCUUAAAAUGUCUGGCUUGAGGUACAAUGAAUGGCUACAAGAUGGAAGUCAGCUGUCCUCCAAUCCUCUGAUGACUCCGGAUAUUCUAGGAUCUUCCGGAGCUGCCGUGCAUACCUGUGUGAAAGCAACCUUCCACGCCUUUAACAAAUACAAGAGAGAGGGGUUUUGCCUUCAGAAUGUUGAUAAGGCCCCUUUGGCUAAGAGAAGAAAAAUGAAAAAGACUAGCACCAGUACCGAGACGCGCAGCAGUUCCAGUGAGAGUUCCCAUUCUUCUUCCUCUCAUUCUCACGGUAAAACUACACCCACCAAGACACUGCAGCCCAGCAAUCCUGCCGACAGCAAUAACCCGGAGACCCUCUUCCAGUUCUCGGACUCAGUAGCUUAGGCAUGGUAGGAGUGUAUCAGUGAUCCAUUGCACCUUUAUUCCCUCAGCAUAUGCCUGAGGCGAUCUUUUAUGCUUUUAAAAAUGUUUCCCGUUGGUCUCAUUGGAAUCUGCCUCCUAAUGAUUUUUUUCAGGAAAACCUGUUUGGUUAUCCUCAUUCAAAAGCACUGGACAGAGAAUGUUACUGUGAAUAGAGCACAUAUUACUCUUUUUAGCAACCUAGCAUGAUGCCAACAAGACUAUUCUUGAAAGAGCAAAGGUUCCUGUAAAUUUAAUUAGGGCUAGAUUUGAGCUGCUUGUAAGUCACAGGUUUUCCAGAUGUCUGCCAACAAGAAAUGACUCAUACUGUGAUGAUACCUUUUGCUUUGCCUUGUGGACAAUGUGGGUUUUUGAAAUUUGCACCCUUCAAACAAUGAUUUAUCAGAGAAAGGGGUCUGUUUUCAAAAAAGAUUCUGUAAUGAAUUUUAUGUGUGGCAUAUACUUAUUUCUUGAGAGAAGAUUUUAACUUAUUGUUUUUAUUUUAUGGUUACAUAUGAUGAUAACCUGCUAUUAUUAAACUUUUUCUAAAAAGUGAAAAAAAAAAAAAAAGAUAUAAGAACUCAAGGUCCCAUACUCUGUAUUCGGGAUCCAUCUGAGAUGCAUGCUAAGCUAUGUGUAUGUUUUUAAUUUUGCACUGCUCUUUCCUGGCAAUUUGUUUUAAUGGUUAUUGCAGAAUAUUAAGGUACAUGUCUCUCUGUUUUAAGUAAUAUUGCACUUUAUAAAAAAGUAUGAAUAAAGCAAACUAUUUUAUAAAGUGCACUGUUUAAAGCAUUUGCACUGUAUUUUUGCCAUUUAUUUUCAUUUUCUACUUUAAAUUUGUCCUCACAUUCCUCUUCUACUUUGUAUGCAACAAGUAGAAUGGGGCAUGUUGUGUCAUGUAGUCAGCCACUUAUGCACCAAUGUGAGGAAAACCUAAAGGGAAAUUAAACUAAACACUGUGCUUCAUAUUUGUACACUGUGUUGUACUACAGUGAGGAAUUUCCUCCUGUAGUCAUAUAUUAUGUACAUAAUAUUUUAGAAUCAUACCUAUGACUUGUUUGGAAAUUUUUCUGUUAAAUUUUAAAUCCAGAAAGCAUAUUUUAUAAACUUAUGCAGAGCACUUUUAUUGCUCAAAAGUUCUGAAUUCAUACAGAAAACAAGUACUAUGUGAUGAAAACAUUUCAUUAAAAGAUUGCUGCAUUUAAAAAUACAAUUAAUUCGUUCCCUAUGCAAAAAAAAAAAAAAAAAAAAAAGAAGUGAUAGGGUUUGUGUGUUAUAUUUUCUUUUAAAGCCAUCAUGUGAAAUGUCAGGACUGAGAAAAGUGAUUUUUUUGCUUUGUUUACAGGAAUCAUGCUUAAAGAGAUAAUGCCCAACAUGUUUAUUUUAUAGUUUUUGUUAAUGAUAACCUUUUGAGCAUUAGUUUGGAAUUUGGACAUGAUAUUUAUUUAUUCCUUUCUUGAGGUUAUAGCAGCAUUAAUUUCAACCAGUUAUGAAUACUAAAAAUAUUGCACUCUAUGUAAUAGUAGUAUAUUUAUUACUAAAUCAAUGUAUAUAUUAAUAGCACAGGCAAAAAAUGGCAAAUAUUAAAAUAUUUUCAAAAUAUUAUAUUAUCCUGUUCACAUUUUGUCCACAGUGGUUAUUGGGAAUAAUAUUUUACACUUUUUGCUGGCCCAAAUGGCUACAUAAUAUUGAGUUAAUGAAAGUUUUCUACUCCCAGCUUUCAGUUAUUCCUAGUAAUUAUGGGAAAUUUUGUGUGAAUUAUUACCAAACUAUUGCUAAUUCACAAAAUGUGAUUCCAUCAGGCACAGAUCUCUAGUAAUCAAGAAAAUGACCAUAUUUAUAAUUAUAUUGGACAUAUUGGGAACAUAUUUGGCUCUUCAAGCCAUUUUUUAAACUGUGCAUCCUGGUAGAAAAUACUAGUUAUAAAGUACAAACUAAAGGGACUAUGUUGCUAAUAGAAAAUGAUCCAGAAAAAUGGUCAGACAGUAUACAGAUUGAUGAUGUGAUUGAUUUCAUUGUGAAUAUUGGAAAUUAAUGGGUUUCAUUUUCAUUUAUUUCCCUUGCCUCUUCUUGAGGAGGAUUCGACAGGCGAUGAAAUGGGUAAAAAGGCAGUCAGACUAACAGGAAGAAGGAAAGAUAGGCUAGCUGUCAACUGAUGAGCCUGCCUGAAUAAUCUCAAAUGGGCUUUUGAAAAGACCUUAACAAACACUGUUGCACUCUUGUCAAAUAUCUUUAUCUACACCCUACUUAUAAGUACCAAAAAGACAGCAUUUGAUGCCAAGUUUGAAGCAGUUAGGUCCUAUGCAGGCUGUGUAUUAACAUACAGUGAAUUGCACUUUAAAAUUCAGAAAGCUUUCAUUUGGUCACAUCAAAAAUAAACACUACAAAAUAUAUAAAAAGUUAAAUGAUAGGACUCUUUUUUUGGUAUUAAGAGUAAAAUAGAAGAAGAUCUAAGAAAUACAAAUACUUACAUUAUUUCUCCUUAUGACAUUAACUUUGGGACUAGAGCCACACCACCCCCUCCCUUCUUCACUUACUGAUUGUAUUGCAUAUAAUUUUCAUGCCAACAUAAAUCCUGAUUCAUAUAUUUUGUAACUGUAUAUGACAAAUUGAGAGGCAAGAAUAAGAAAAGGAAGAUAAUAGAGGAAAGAUGUUAAGAAAGACCAGUUUCUUCUAAUUACUCUGCCAGAUCGUGUGUCUGAAAGAGGUUAAUUAGCAUUUUGAAAUUGAUUGGCUGAGUGUGGUGGCUCAGGCCUGUAAUCCUUGUGCUUUGGGAGUAUAAGACUGGAGAAUCACUUGAAACCAGGAGUUAGAGACCAACCUGGGCAACAUAGUGAGACACUGUCUCUCCAAAAAUAAAAAUAAAAAUUAGCUGAGCAUGGUGGCUCAUGGGAGGCCAACAUGUGGAGGAUCGCUUGAGCCCAGGAGUUCGAGGCUGCAGUGAGCUGUGAUCACACCACUGCACUCCAGCCUGGGCAACAGAGCGAGACCCUGUCUUAAGAAAAAAAGAAAUUCAUUAAUUCUUCCAAACCUUUAUAAAGUAAGAAACCACUGAAUUACUAGAAUAGAAAGUCAGUCUCCUGAGUUAAUUUCCACAUUGUUGUCUGUCUUGGAGUCACAGGUUCAUUACCCAAGAAAACUGCCUUUUAAUUUUUUUAGAUUACUGUUGAUUUCUUAAGUAUGUAAAUGACUAACUUUUAAAUAUAAGGUAAGUUAUUUUAAAGAAAUCUACUAAGAUAGAAGUCACUUUUUUUAAAGUAAGGAAAUUCCUUUUGUAUCUCAGUUUAUGUUCUCAAAUACACUACUUUAUAAAAGUAUACAAUUGACUGGAUACUUAUUCACCUUGCCCCCAUUUCAAGCGCCUGUUAUUGUCAUAUUUAUUAAAAACAGGGUACCUCAUAAUGGUGAAAAUUUCUAAAUUAUUGGGUCUAUAUGUGCCUUAGACUGCCUGAUUACUUUGGCUGUUCUCCCAGUGACUGAUAAUAAUAGCAUGAUUUGAGUGUUCAUGUGAGAAUACAUCUAAUAUUCCUUAAGAUCUAAGUAAAUAAGUUAAAUUCUGAUAUGCCACUUAUGUCAAAAUAAUUGUUAUAUAGAUGAAUUAUUACUGUAACAUCAUGAAGUAUCUUAAAAUUAUAUGACUUUUGGCCUCUCAAAUGUCUUACAUGAUAAUACCCCAAUUUCCAGUCUUUAAUUGAUUGUAUACCUCACGUAAGUGUCUGUCAUCACUUGAUACCUGUAUCUGGCACUAAAACAAAUGUAGCCGGCUCUAAUGAAAUUUGAAGUUUGGAUAGGAGACAUUGUAAAACUCAAGAAUGGGAAAAAAAAAUUUUAACAGAAGUAUGUAUGAAGGAAAUAUUUUAAGUAUAAUCUACCCAAAGAAAAUAACUGCUACAGCCAACAUUAAAGGUUUUAUUCCCUGUUUUGUUAAGUAACUUCACUCCAAAUUGUGACAUUCUUUAGAGAAAAUAUUUUCCUUAAGAGUAGUUAUUUACGUGUUUUAUUGGGGGAGCAUAUUUUCAGGGGGGCAACAUCUUGCUAAGAACAUUUGAUUAGCCUCACUUCUGUCCUCACCUUCUAUAUUGCUUACUUUUCAAGAUAUUUCUUCUGAGCCCUUUUCUUUGUAUGCCCAGCUCCCUGUUAUGUAAUUAAGUAGUUGAUUACCAUUCCAAAUGCUUCCCCUACACAAGGCUGUUGUCCACCCUGUUUCAUGAAUUUGUGAAUUAAGUAGGUGCCUAAUAUUUUCCUACUAUUAGGGUGAAAAGGAAUAAGAAACUAAAGUGGCUUCCAAAUGUUUGUGUCUUGGUUUCUUCACCCUAGUGCAAAAUAGGAAAUGUUUAUUGGCAGUCAUUUCUUUUCCAUUACUCCUUUUAACCACAUUACAAAAAGCUAGGAUUUUGUGUCUAGAAGGAGACUUGUAUUAAAAGACAAGAUUCUUAGUAGUUAUUCAUCAGGCUUAAGUUUCCUGGUGUAUUUCUUGUGGGAGAGGUAGAAGGACAUUUUGUAGUAGUAUUCUAACUAUUAAUAUAAUGCUGCUUGGGUUAUCAGAAAGUAUUGAAUACUUCAGAUAAGUCAAGUUAGUAUUUAGUAUAGCAGCUGUUCUUCAGAGCACAGGAAACUGGGAUAGUAUGUAGUAUUAUGCUGUUUCCAUUAUUGUUUCUCAUUGCAUAACACUUUUAAUUUAUAUGUUGGUAUACAAUUUGCCCCUUUACUAAAAAAAAAAAUCUAGUUUCAUUCUUGUUCCUUGCCACAUUAAGCAGUUUUUUCAUUUACGUUUUAAAUUUUCUUAAUAUUAGAAGAAAAAGAAAACAGAACAAAAGAGAAAUGUCAUGACUUAGAAAAGGAAAUUUUAAGUUUUAUGGAAUACUGUAGCUUUAUUUUCUGACAUUUCUGCUUAUAGAUAGAUUAGAAAAUCCUUGUUUCUUUUGUUUGCUUUGUUUUAAAAUCCAGUAAGGUUGAGGAACUUGACAUUUUAAAACUGCAGUUUUAUUUUUAACUACAUAAGAGGCUGGUCAUGUGAAAUGUGCACUGCUAUGUUGGAAUGGAUAUGUAUGUGACAAUUAACCUCAUUAAAGCUCUGUUGCUGUGGUAGGCAUUCAGUUAUUCCUAAUAGUUUAUUUUAGGUACUAUACUGCUAUCCUAUUUGCUGAAAUUAUAAAUACUAGCAAUGUACAAUAAUUCUCAUUCUUUGGCUGAAUAAAAACAGAAAUUUAAAGGUGCUGUGUCACAUAAACAGUUAAUGCCUCAGUACUAAAGUUUUGAAAAAUAUUCCUAAAAACUUCACAGGCAUGAAUUUUUGAAAAGAAGAAGAAACCACAUAUACACAUAGAGGAAUUUUUAAAGACUGGCAUUUUAAAGUAUAGCUGGUAAAAAUGGUAUGUAUCCUUAUGUGUAGAAUUUAAACUUCUUGAAAAUAAUCUAAGCUGCAACAAUCUAUGUAACUGCUCUUCCACAGUUUUACAUAAAGAUAAGAAUUUGUCUUACUAAAAGGUAAAUGGAAGAUUAAAAAAGAUGAAAAACAUUGUUUUUCCUCUAUUCUAUGUGGACAAUUAAAAGUAUAGCCAAGCCUCAGCUCAAAUGAGUUGCCUUUGUGUGAGACAGGGUCUCACUCUGUCACCCUGGCCGGAGUGCAGUGGCGUGAUCACAGCUCACUGCAACCUCCACCUCCUGGGCUCAAGCAAUCCUUGUACCUCAGCCUCCUAAGCAGCUGACUAAGUAGACUACAGGCAUGAGCCACCAUGCCCAGCUAAUUUUUUUUUAAUAGCUACAAGGUAUCAGUAUGGUGCCCAGGCUAGUCUCAAACUCCUGGCUUCAAGCAAUCCUCCCGCCUCAGCCUCCCAGCUUUGCCCAGCCGUGAGUUGCUUUGUGAGUUGUCUUCCUUAACUGCAUCAGUUCAUCCCAUACUCCGUACAUGCACUUUUUCUCGUAUUUUUCUGCUUUUCUAUGGUGUGUCCACACUCAUUUGUGUAUUUCUACACUGGUAUUUCACUACUUAUUAAGAUAUCUGCAUGUGGACCUACAUUUAUAAAUUGUAAUUCCGUUCAGAGAAAUAAGAACUUGAUUGGGACAGAGCUGGGAAAUGUUUGUGAUGAAAAUUAUUAGGAAUAAGGAAAUAAUGAUGCUGUGUGAGAAAGCAAGUAGACUUAAAUUCUGAGAUAGAAACAUCUGCAAUCAACAUAGAGAAGGCUACUUUACAAAAAUGUUAUUUCAGUGCCCGUAUGGACAAAUCUCUUUAAAAGGCUUUGUCUACUGUGUACAUAAAGGAACUUAUAAGCUUCAUAAAGUGCUUAUUUUUCUCUAGGAAGCCCAUGUGAUAGCUCUCUCCUCUGUUUUCCCACUCCUUCCCCAGCUUUUCCUGCUGCCCACUGCUCCAAACACUGACAUCCAGUGGCCAGAGACCAGUCCAAAUGGAGCACUAAAACUACAUAUAGAUAGUGAUCAUAUUGUUUAAAAUGUUAUUGCAACAUGGUGUGUAAAGUGCACAGGUCUGAAAUAUACAGCUCAAUAAAUGUUUACAUAUAUAUGCGCCCAUAUAACCAUCAUUCAGAUCAAGAUGAGGCUCCCAGUCAGUCCUCAUACAUAACCACCACUCUGACCUCUGUCACUGUUGUUGACAUUCCUAUACAUGGAAUUAUCCAGUCUAUAGGUUUUUGUGUCUGGUUUAAUUUGAUCAGCAUUAUGUCUGUGAAAUGCAUCUAUGUUGUUGCAUGUAGCAAUAACAGUAGUUUGUUCUUUUUCGUUGCUCUGUAGUAUUCCAUCAGAUAAAUACAUCACAAUUUAUCCAUUCUCCCACUGAUAGACAUUUUGGUUGUUUGUAAUUUUUAGCUUUUGUGUUUAAAGCAGCCAUAAGCAUUCUUGUGCAUAUAUUUUAAUGGACACGUACACUCAUUUCUCUUGUGUGUCCACUUAAAAGUGAAACAGCUGGCUGCAGUGAGCCUUGAUCGCACCACUACAUUCCAUCCUGGGCGAUAGAGUGAGACCCUGUCUCAAAAAAACAGACAAAAAAAAGGAGUGAAACUACUGAGUCAUAAGAUGAAUAUAUAUUUAGCUGUAGAAGAUAUUACCAAAUGGUUUUCAACAAUGGUUGUACCAAUUUACAUACCCACCAAUAAUGUGUAAGUGUUCUAGUUCUUCCACAUCCUCAUCAGUGCUUGGUACCAUCAGCCCUAGUAGUUUAGCCACUCUGACAAAUGUGUAUAUUUGAUUGUGGUUUUAACCAUUCUGGUGAUUUUGUAUUUCACUGAGAUUUUAAGGUGUAUUUUCCUGAUAAGUAGUGAUGUGUGGAACACCUUUUUAUAUUUUUAUUAGUCAUUUGGCUAUCCUCAAUUAAGUGCCUGUUCAAGUCAUUUGUUCAUAUUUAUUGGGUUGUCUUUUUUUCUUACUGACUUGCAGGAGUCUUUUAUAUUUUAUGGAUAUGAGGGUUUUUGUCUGAUAUUUUACCAUAAAUGUCUUCUCUUUAGUUUGCUUUUCUACUUUCUAAGUGCUUUCCUUUGAUGACCAAAAAUUUUAUGAAGUCCAAUAUACCAGUCUUUUAUUUAAUUGCUAAUACUUUUGCGUCGUAUUUAAUAAAUGUUCACACCAAGGUUAUGAAGAUAUUCUUAUAUUCUUCUAAAAGCUUUAUUGGCCGGGUGAGGUGGCUCAUGCCUGUAAUCCUAGUGCUUUGGGAGGCCAAGCCAGGUGGAUCACUGGAGGUCAGGAGUUGGAGACCAGCCUGGCCAACAUGGUGAAACCCCAUCUCUACUAAAAGUAUAAAAAUUAGCCAGGCAUGGUGGUGCAUGCCUGUAAUCCCAGCUACGUGGGAGGCUGAGGCAGGAGAAUCGCUUGAACCCAGGAGGCAGAGGUUGCAGUGAGCCAAGGUCAUGCCACUACACUCUAGCCUAGGCAACAGAGCGAGACUCUGUCUCAAAAAAUAAAACUAAAAGCUUUAUUGUUUUACCAUCCACAUUAGGUUUACAGUCCAUCUACUGCUGAUAUUUGUAUAUGAUGUGAAAUAGUAGCCAAAGUUUAUGUAUUUCCAUAUGAGUAUUAACUUGACCCAGCACAAUGUAUUGAAAAGCUGAGUUGUAAUUUUUAUGAAGUCUUCAUAUCUGGUAGUGUAAGACCUCUAACUUUUAUCUAAUAGUUCUAAUAGUUUUGGCUAUUCUUAAUCCUUUGCAUUUCCAUAUACAUUUUAGAAUCACCUUGUUAGUUUUGGGGGCAGAGGAUGUUAGGGUUUAAUUGGUAUUGCAUUGAAUGUAUAAAUCAAUUUCAGGAGAAAUUAUAUCUUACCAAUUUUGAGUUUUCCAAUGCAUGGACAUGGUAUAUCCCUCUAUUUACUUAGGUAUUUAAUUUGUCUCACCAGUGUUUUAUAGAUUUACAUGUAGAGGUUAGAUUUAUAUCUAGGUUUUUGACAGUUUUACUUUAUUAUCAAAUUGUUUUUAAUUAGUUUAUAGAAAUAUAGUUUUUUUGGUAUAUUACCCUUUCACUUAGAAACCUUGUUAAAUUCACUUUUUAAUUCUAAUCUGUAUAUUAUUUUAGAUUUCUUUAAGUCUACAGUUAUAUCGUCUGUAAAUAAUGACAGUUUCAUUUCUGCCUUUUCAAUUUUUAUUUUUCUUGCCUUAUUGAGCUGAUCAGGACCUCCAAUAACAUGCUAAAUGAAGUAAUGACAAUGGACUCCUUAAACUUCUUCAACUCAGAAUAAGAAUUCAAUAUUUUUCUAUUCUAUAUAUAUAUAUUUUUUUCUUUUCUUUUCUUUUUUUUUUUUUUUUUUUUUUUUUUUUGAGACGGAGUCUCGCUCUGCCACCCAGGCUGGAGUGCAGUGGCUCAAUCUCAGCUCACUGCAACCUCCACCUCCCAGGUUCAAGUGAUUCUUCUGCCUCAGUCUCCCGGGUGGCUGGGACCACAGGCAUGCACCACCACCCUCAGCUAAUUUUUGUAUUAUUAGUAGAGAUGGGGUUUCACCAUAUUGGCCAGACUGGCCUCGAAUUCCUGACCUCGUGAUCCACCCGCCUCAGCCUCCCAAAGUGCUGAGAUUACAGGCAUGAGCCACCUCACCCAGCCCAAUAUUAUGUUUUAUUUAAUUUUUUUAUAGAUAUCAUAUAGCAGAUUGUUUUAUUUCUAAUUUUCAGAGAGUUUUUACUAAAUGCUUUUUCUGCCUCUGUUGAGAUAAUCUUGUAUUUUUCUUCUUUAUUCUUCAAUUUUCAAAUGCUGAAAAUAGAAUAAAUUCCAUUUUCAUGAUGUAUUGCCCUUUUCAUAUAUCAAUGGAUAUAGUUUGCUAAUAUUUUGCCUAAGAUUUUUGGAUCAUAAGGAGGAUAGACCUAGACUGGGUGUGGUAUCUCACACCUGUAAUCCCAACACUUUGGGAGGCCAAGAGGAAGGAUUGCUUUAGCCCAGGAGUUGGAGACCAGCCUGGGCAACAUAGAGAGACCUCAUCUCUACAAAAGAUUAAUUAGCCAAGGAUGGUGGUGCACACCUGUAGUACCAAAUACCUGGGAGGCUGAGGUGGGAGAAUCACUUGAGUCCAGGAAGCAGAAGUUGCAGUGAACCAAGAUUGUACCACUGUACUCCCACCUGGGCAACAGAGCAGGAGCCUAGCAUUAAAAAAAGAAGAAGAAGAAGAAGAAGAAGGAGGAGGAGGAGGAGGAGGAGGAAGAAGAAGGACAGACCUGUAAUUUUUCUGUCUUUAAUAUUUUUGUCAAGUUUUGGUAUCAAGAUUAUUCUGGCCUCAUAAAAAAAAAGUUGGAGAUGUGUUCCCUUUUUUUCUACACUCUGGAAGAGUUUGCACCUGAUAUUAUUCCUCCUGUUUAAAAUAAUUCACCAUUGAAGCCACUUGAAUGAGAAGUUUUCUUUGUGGGAAAGUUGUCAUUAAUUGGAAUAUAUCUUGUCUACUUACAGUUAAUGUAAUUAUUAUUGGUUUUAAGUCUACCAUCUUACAAUUUCUUUUACAUUUUUGUCCUAUAUCCUCUUGGUUCCUGUAUUGUGUCUUCUUUUGAUAAACCAAAUAUUUUCUUUUGUCCAUUGUUUCCUCCUAUGUUAGUUCGUUAGUAAUUUUUAGAAAUUCAUUUAGUACCUUAAAGAUUACAGCUUGUAUCUUUGACUUGCUGCCUUAAAUUGGUACAUUACCACUUCCCAACAAUGCAGGAAUUUUAUGACAGUUUAAAUCUGUUUUCCCCUUUUUUUUUUUUUUUUUUGAGAUGGAGUCUUUGUCGCCAGGCUGCAGUGCAGUGGCACGAUCUUGGCUCACUGCAACCUCUGAUUCCCUGGUUCAAGCGAUUCUCCUGCCUCAGCCUCCCGAGUAGCUGGGAUUACAGACACAAGCCAGCACACCCAGCUAAUUUUUGUAUUUUUAGUAGAGACGGGGUUUCACCAUGUUGGCCAGGAUGGUCUAGAUCUCCUGACCUCGUGAUCUGCCCACCUCAGCCUCCCAAAGUGCUGGGAUUACAGGUAUUCCCCCUUCUUCCUUUUAUGUUAUUGUUGUCAUGUAUUUUACUUCUACAUUCUAUGUAUGUUUUAUCUCUAUAUAUGUGUUUUAGACUUCAUAAGACAUUAUUUUUUUUUUUUUGAGACAGAGUCUCGCUCUGUCGCCCAGGCUGGAGUGCAGUGGCGGGAUCUCGGCUCACUGCAAGCUCCGCCUCCCGGGUUCAUGCCAUUCUCCUGCCUCAGCCUCCCAAGUAGCUGGGGCUACAGGCGCCUGCCACUACGCCCGGCUAAUUUUUUGUAUUUUUAGUAGAGAUGGGGUUUCACCGUUUUAGCCGGGAUGGUCUCGAUCUCCUGACCUCGUGAUCCGCCCGCCUCGGCCUCCCAAAGUGCUGGGAUUACAGGCGUGAGCCACCGCGCCCGGCCGACAUUAUUUUUAUUAGUAGUACUACUACUAUAUAUUUUAAAGACUCUGGCUGGGCACUGUGGCUCACGCCUGUAAUCCCAGCACUUUGCGAGGCCAAGGCAGGUGGAUCACCUGAGGUCAGGAGUUCGAGACCAGCCUGGCUAACAUGGUGAAACCCCGUUUCUACUAAAAAUACAAAAAAUGAGCCAGGAGUGGUAGUGCAUGCCUGUAAUCCUAGCUACUUGGGAGGCUGAGGCAGGAGAAACGCUUGAACCCGGAAGAGGGAGGUUGCAGUGAGCCAAGGUCGCACCAUUGCACUCCAGAUUGGGCAACAAGAGCGAAACUCCAUCUCAAAAAAAAAAAAAAAAAAAUAGACUCUAUAUUGUUUGUUUGCUCACAUAUUUAUGUUUUCUGGUGUUUUUCUUUCCAUCCUGCCUUUUUUACUUCCAUCUGGGAUUACUUUUCUUCAUCUGGAGAAUUCUCUUUAGUAUUUAUUUUAGUGCCAGUCUUCUGACAAUGAAUUCUCUCAGCUUUUGUUUUUUGAAACCUUCUUUCUUUUGCCUUUAUUUUUCUGUAUUUUUAUUUUUUUAAGAUAAAAUUCAUGUAUCAUGUAAUAUACCCAUCUAAUCAUUCCAUUCAGAUACAAUUCAAUGUUACCUUUAUUUUUGAAGGAUAUUUUUGCCUUGUAUGAAAUACUAGGUUCACCAUUUUAUUUUAUUUUAUUUUUGAGACCAAGUCUCACUCUGUCACCCAGGCUGGAGUGCAGUGGCACAAUCUUGGCUCACUGCAACCUCCACCUCCUAGGUUCAAGUGAUUCUUGUGUCUCAGCCUCCCAGGUAGCUGGGAUUACAGGCAUGCACCACCACGCCUGGCUAAUUUUUGUGUUUUUAGUAGAGAUGGGGCUUCACCACAUUAGCGAGGCUGGUCUCAAACUCCUGACCUCAAGUGAUCUGCCCACCUCGGCCUCCCAAAGUGCUGGGAUUACAGGUGUGAGCUACUGGCGCCCAGCCUAGGUUCACCAUUUUCAAGAUAUCAUUCCAAUCCUUAAGUUCUGUGGAAAAAGCCAUUAGUUAUAUUUCCUUUGAAGGUAAUGUGUCUUUUUUCUGUGGUCACUUUUAAGAUUUUCUCUUCGUCUUUGUUUUUAUUUUUUAUUAUACUUUUAAGUUCUGGGUUACAUGUGCAGAACGUGCAGGUUUGUUACAUAGGUAUACACGUGCCCUGGUGGUUUGCUGCACCCAUCAACCUGUCACCAAAUUAGGUAUUUCUCCUAAUGUUAUCCCUCCCCUAGCCCCCAACCCCCCGACAGGCCCCAGCGUGUGAUGUUCCCCUCCCUGUUUCCAUGUGUUCUCAUUGUUCAACUCCCACUUAUGAGUGAGAACAUGCGGUGUUUAGUUUUCUGAUCUUUUGAUAGUUUGCUGAGAAUGAUGGUUUCCAGCUUCAUCCAUCCUAAGAUUGGUAAACUUCCUGAAUCUGUUGGUUGAUGUCCUUCCUUAUUAGAAUUCUUAACCAGUCAUUCUUCAAAUAGUUUUUUCCAAUCCGUUUUCUCUCUCCCGUUUUCUAGGAUUGUGUGUUAUACUAUGUUCCAUAUGUCUGUUAUAGUCCUUUGUUUGCCAUCUUAAUUUCUCCCUGUACUUCAAUCUGUAUAGUUUUUACUGACCUAAUUAACUUAUCCUGUUCUGCUGAGCCUAAUCAAUUUUAAAUUUAGUUGUAUAUCUUAUAUUUUGGAUUCUAAAAUAUCCAUGACACUUUUUUGUAGGUGCCAAGUCUCUGAUCAUAUCUUGUCUUUUCCUCUAUAUUCUUGAACACAUUAAUCAAAGUAAUUUUAAAACUCUUGUCUGAGAAAUCCAGUGUCUGAUUACUACUACUAGUUGUUUGUUUCCAUUGUCUGUUGUCAGUCAUUUGGUGCUGUUUUUUAGCAUGCCUUAUAAGUUUGGUGAAAUGUCAUACAUUGUGUGUUAAAUACUGUAGGGGCUUUGAACGAUGUUAUCUUCCUCUAAGAUGGUUAUGUUUUCUUCUUGCAGUCUGAUAAAAUACAGGCAUAUCACUGUAAUCCUAUUGAAGGUUGGUUUUAGACUUUGUUGGGCUUGUACAUUUCAGUUUUGCUCUUACUCCUAGCAUAUGGCCUCUUUGGGCUCUCAUCUGAAAAUCUAGGGUGUUUAUCAGGGCCACUUCACCUCGGUGACCUUGAAUUCCAACCUUUCCCUCCUCAGUACUAAGAGCUGCUCAGCUCGUUAGCCUCUCAUCUGCUGCUUUUUGCUGGAUUUCUUGAAGUCUCACCUUGUUGCACAGGAGUCUGCAAUUGGCAGACACCUCAAGGAGAUACUGUACCAGUAUUUCAGGCUCACUUCCCUGAGGUUUCUUCGCUCUGGGAUUUUGCCCCUUAAGUCCUAGCUACUUUCCCAAGCUCCAACUUUUGUCUCUUCAACCAAGUGGGAUUACUGCUUGCUGCUAGGUAUUUAUUUCCCUGUGUUGUGAAUUUGCAGUGCCUUGAAGAAGUAAUCAAAAUGAACACAGAGCUCACCAAAGUGUGCUUCCCUUUUUUCCCUCCUUUCAGCUAUUUUAUUGCAGCUCGUCAAGUUCUCCCUGCAUUGGUUUGCUCCCUGUUGCCUAUAAAAGAUGUUCUACUUAACCCUUUUCCUGUUUGCCCCAAGAAUACUUGCCAGCAGCACUUGCUGCUGCAGUAUUUACCCCAAGAUAACUUUGCCACGAACUCUCGCUUUUAUUAUUACUUUCGUUUAGCUCUAGUAUAUUGACUUCAGAAAAAAAGGACAUCGUUCUCUUUAUAGCAUUCUGUUCUUAGUAGUGGUAUUUCCAUUUACAAAGUAUAAUAAUUCUCGAUCGCUGAAAAUGUCGAAUCCUAGAAAAUGUAGCAUUCCUACACGUGAUGUUAACAUCAUUCUCGAACAGUUCUUGGACAGAGAUUUAUUUAAUGAAUUCGAUUUUUCUGAAAUAGAUGAUUUUGAUGAUUCAGAUGCUUCUGAUACUAGAUCUGUUUAGAAAUAACAUCAAGAACAGUUUUUAUAUUUUAUUUUCACAUUGAAAAUCAGUCAGAUUUGCUUUAGCCUCAAAGAAUGUGUUUACGUAAAAUUAAAUGAAUGCUGGCAGUGAGCUGUACUUUUUUUUUCUAAACCGGAAAAGGGUUAAUAUAGCUUUCAUCGUUGUUUUCAGUAGGAGGGCUAGUCCAAUCACAAGCUACUCUAUUGUGGCCAAAAGCAAAAAUCUGGUGGUAAUCAUUUUUAAUCGCCAUUGUUGAUUUCUCCGCAGUGGCUUCUGGCAUUGAUAACUUGGUUGUCACAUGGUCAUAUGUGAAGGCACCCGGUUUAUUCAUUUGUUCCUUUGUCCAUUAAAUAGUUUUUGAGCACUUCUUUCAGGCCAGGUAUUACUCUAGACACAAGCAAUAUAACAAUAUUUAAGAUAAGAUCUGUGUCACUUUGGCACUUGCAGCCUGUUUUUAUAGAAAGGCUACUAAAUGGUUGCCGAGUCGGACUUGUGGUAAUUAAAAUAGACUUUUCUUGUGUGGGGGUUGGGAGUGAGAAAAAAGAGACUGGAAUCUUUUAGAUGAUUACAUCUUCUUUAUAUAAAUAUUUUUAGCCUUUUGAAAAAACUCUGUAGAGCUUAAUGCAGUUCACAGUUCACCCACACUACAUCAAUAUUUGGCCUACCUUUUGCAAGCCCAAUUCCCUAACUAUGAGUUUCUGUGUUACAUAAAAAUCUCACCGGGAGCACAAUUAUUUGACAAUUUGAGUUGAAACUCCAGGAACUGAUUUAUGGAGAACAAACUUAGCUCUGAAAUUAUGUCUCUUUAUGAAUAUCGACAUGAAAUCUGAUGAAGAAUCAUCCUACUGUGGUUUCCCAUUUUAACUUCUGUUUUUGAAAAACAUUUCAGAUGCAACUAAGCACUUAUUAAAUGCUUCGUGAUACCAAAAAAUGGCUUGGUGGUCUUUGUCUUCCAGAAUAGCAUAAAUUUCAGUGUUACCAAGAUAAAAAUAUAAUCUGGGCACAUGUCACUGUUAAAAUAUUAUAGUCAGAUCAAGGAUUCUAUUCCUGUCUUUGUUAUUCUUUCCCACUUUUGAAACUUUAUCCAGUGGAUUUUUUUUUAUUACAAAGACGUAUUCCAGAGAUAACAGUUUGUACUUCUGAUUAUGAUCCAUGUUCAUGUGAUCAAAAGGCAGCAAUAAUAGGACACUGUCAUAUAUGGUAGCUCCAUAGAAACUAGGCUGCACUGGGAGGACAGAUUCGCCAUCUUGAGCACCUGUGGCUUGGUAUUCUCGAAAUUGUAGCCCCUUUGGAAUGGCUGAAGAACUACCAGUUAAAGGUAAAGAAACCAGACACACAAGGCCACGUAUUGUAUGAUUCCACUUACAUGAAAUGUCCAGAAUGGGCAAAUCCAUAGAGACAGAAAGAUUAGUGUUUUUCAGGGGCUGGUGGGAGGGGGAAAUAGGGAGUGACAAUGUAUACAGGUGAUGGGGUUUUGGGGUGAUCAAAAUGUUCUGGAAUUAGGUAGUGGUAAUGGUUGCAAGACAUUGUAAAUGUAGUAAAAAACAAUGAAUGGUACACUUAAAAUGAAUUUUAUCUUAUAUUUUAAAAAAUCACACACAGGCCGUGCACAGUGGCUCACGCCUGUGAUCCCAGCACUUUGGGAGGCCGAGACGGGUGGAUCACCUGAGGUCAGGAGUUGGAGAACAGCCUGACCAAAAGGGAGAAACUCCAUCUCUAAUAAAAUACAAAAAUUAGCCGGGCGUGGUAGCGCAUGCCUGUAAUCCCAGCUACUUGAGAGGCUGAGGCAGGAGAAUCACUUUAACCCGGGAGGCAGAGGUUGCAGUGAGCCUAGAUCGCACCAUUGCACUCCAGCCUGGGCAACAAGAGUGAAACUCCGUCUCAAAAAAAAAAAAAAAAAAAAUCACGCAUAGCUAGAAAGGCUGUAGCUAGUUUGAGGAAGUCAGUACUAACACCUGGCUAUUCAGAGAAUGCCAUCCUGCCCCCCUUUCUUUGGCAUCAACUCUGAAGCAUAGUUAUGUUAUGGUUGGAAAAUCUUUUCUAACUAGAGAUUAAGCUCUUGGGGACAAAGUAAACUUGCCUCUUACAGGAAACACCAAAGUUCCAGCUUAACAGAGAAAGGGAACCUCCUUGGGAAUCAUACUUUUCCCAUUAUUGGGUAGUGCUCGGACAGAUGUCAAAGUGCUGUAUGUUUCCAUGGUGAUCAUAUCCAGCUUAUCAUUACUUGUAUCUUUGCCCUAAAGUUUAAUUUCUUACUUUGGGACUCAUUAUAAUAAUGGGAGCACCGGCCUUUUGGGAGGCCAAGGCGGGUGGAUCACGUGAGGUCAGGAGUUUGAGAGCAGCCUGGCCAACAUGGCGAAACGCUGUCUCUACUCACGCCUGUAAUCCCAGCACUUUGGGAGGCUGAGGCGGGCGGAUCACGAGGUCAGGAGAUCGAGACCAUCCUGGCUAACACGGUGAAACCCCGUCUUUACUAAAAAUACAAAAAAUUAGCCGGGCGUGGUGGCGGAUGACUGUAGUCCCAGCUGCUCGGGAGGCUGAGGCAGAAGAAUGGCGUGAACCUAGGAGGCAGAGCUUGCAGUGAGCCGAGAUCGCGCCACUGCACUCCAGCCUGGGCAACAGAGCAAGACUCUGUCUCAAAAAAAAAAAAAUACAAAAAUUAGCUGGGCGUGGUGGUGGGUGCCUGUGGGCCCAGCUACUUGGGAGGCUGAGGCAGGAUACUCUCUUGAACCCAGGAAGCAGAGGUUGCAGUGAGCCGAGAUCACGCCAUUGCACUCCAGCCUAAGCGACAGAGUGAAACUCCGUCUCAAAAAAAUAAAAAAUAAAAAAUAAUGUAAGUACCAGGCCUUUGUUUGAGUUCAGUUUUUCUUUGGUGAGCACUUUUCUAAAAUCUCUCUCAUCUUACCUAUGUUAACUUUGUCUCAGAAGCAGGCUCAUUUGUGCAGUUAGCUGAAAUAUUUAUUCAGAAAGUCAUUUAUAGCAGUUGUCUUUUCAUCAAACAUAAUACCUUUAAAAUAGCAGAAAAUUAAUGCCAUUCAUGAUUUUGCCAUUUUACUAAGUAGUCAGAAGCUAUGUCUCCCUUAGCCCCAUCAUAUACAUUUGAAAUAUCUUUAUCCUAGAUAAUCUGUAUUCAUUUGAAUGCAAAAGUUUUAUCAAUAUGAGUGAACUUAUACAUCUUUUUAUUCGCUGAUGGAGAUAUCACUUGAAACUUUGUUCCUGGCAAAGCAAAGAGAUGAAAUGUAUUGAAAAAAAUCGAUUAGACUUUUAAAACUUCAAAAUACUUUUAUAGAAAAUGUAAAUAAGAUUGUUUCUAACUGCAGAGUGUUUUACAUAAAAUCUUUAUGUGAAGAAUUUAUAUUGCAGUACAAUAAAGUCAGUGCUUUUUAUAUGUUUUGAAUGGUAAACAUUUUGAAGGUAUUUUUUGAAGUAACUAGGUAUUGACAUUUUUUAAUAAUAUAUUUUGAAUAAAGCACACCUAAAAUGCAUGAACUUGUGUAAGUAUUUGGCAUCAUUAGUCUAGUUGUACAUAUUUUUAAAAAUAAGAAUGGGCUUAGAAGAUAAUGUAUUUGUAGUAAGUAUAGUAUAUUUUUUACUGAGUGAGUCUGAUACGUCUUUUAGAUAUUUGAGUAAAGUCUACUGUUAAAGUAUUCCAGAUUUUUAAAUUCCAGUGUCCUUGCUGUGGAAUCUAGUGUUGGCUUUCUGAUGUCAGAAUAAUCAAACCCUGCUCAUAUACACAUCCAGAAAACUUUUUCUAAUGAUGAUACAUUUAGCAAAAUCGCAAGUCUUUAAAAAUUCUAGUUAAAUAGACUUACUUGAGACAAGUGUACAUUGUGAAAUCUAAAAUAAAAAUUUGUGACUAUAUAAUACAUAAUCUUCAUUAUGUAGGCUAUUUCUAAAAACUUAGUUUCUGUGCUGAUUUCAUGUUAAGUUUUUCAAACGUUAGCAGAUUAUAAUGGCUACAGUAAGUUUUGUUCUAAAUCUGGUAGCCAUUUAUUAUUAAAUGAUUAAUGAUUAAACAUUAAUCAUUUAAUAAUUACUUAGGAAUUAUAAAUUACAAUGUCAAAUCUUCAUACAUCAGGCUCCUUGCACUAUAAUUACUUAAAAUUAGUUUGCAUCAAUAGUCUAUAUAAACAGAUAUCUUAGUUUAGAGGAAAAAAUAUUCUAUUUUCUAGGUACUUUAAUAGUUUGGUCUUGUGAAAAUUACAUAGGUGUGUGUUUAUGUAUGUGUAUACACACAUGUAUUGGGGGCUUACAAUACCAAAUUAAUAAGACUGCCCCUCACUCCUUAAAUCGACUAUCUGCCCUGCCAGUAAUCCCCCACCUGUACUGGUAUAUACAGAGUUUUCUCUGGUACAAAUGAUUAAUCAAGAAAAAGGGUGUGAAAUAUUUGUGUUCGUUUCUUUUUAAAUGAAUAAUGGGAUACACAUAAACUAGUAACACCACAUUGAUUUCCUAAAGACCUAAUACAGCUUUAAGAGGGAAUAACAUUCCAGAGCUCCAGGAUUAUUUUAAUUUAGCUUUCAAGAUGGUUACGAUUUUGAUUUAAUAUAGAGACUUCAUAGUGUUAAAUUUUAGGGUUUUUUUUUUUUUUUUUGUAUUUUUAGUAGAGAUGGGGUUUCACCAUGUUGGUCAGGCUGGUCUCGAACUCCUGCCCUGAUGAUCUGCCUGCCUCGGCCUCCCAAAGUGCUGGGAUUACAGGCGUGAGCCACUGUGCCCAACCUAAAUUUUAGGUAUUUAAAACAUCCAUUGAUGCUUUGUUUUGUUUUUGGGUUUUUUUUUUAUUGUUGUUACUUAAGGGAUGCAUCUUAUUUAUUUGGUUGACUUUUAUCUAGACAUCAUAAAUGUGAUGCUUACUUUUUUAUUAGCCACUUCAUUGUUGAUGUCUUAAUGGGAGAUCUUAGUUUGAUGAAUCUACUCUUUGAAAUUUUAGUUUGAUUAGUCAUUUGUUUCUGCUAGGUUUUGGCUUUUGUUUUGUUUUUUGAGUGAUAACCUAAGAAGUUUCUACAGUGGAAAAUAUCAUUAUGACAUCUUCAUCCCUUAUAAAGUUGUUUCAUUUAGAGGAAUUUUUCAAAGCCUAUGUUGAGAAAUGGGCAAAUUAAGUAAAGCAUCAUAACAAUUUUUUUUAUAGUGAACUCAUUUUAUUUAUAGAACGGCAAACACAUUCACUCUUUUUGCUAACAUCCGGGGCUUUUUUCAUUGUGACUGCUUUGCACACUUAAAAAUGUUUCUCCCAGGCCGGGCACGGUGGUUCAUGCCUGUAAUCCCAGCACUUUGGGAGGCCGAGGCGGGCGGAUCACAAGGUCAGGAGAUUGAGACCAUCCUGGCUAACAUGGUGAAACCCUGUCUCUACUAAAAAUACAACAAAAAUUAGCCGGGCGUGGUGGCAGGCGCCUGUAGUCCCAGCUACUGGGGAGGCUGAGACAGGAGAAUGGCAUGAACCCGGGAGGCGGAGCUUGUAGUGAGCCGAGAUCGCGCCACUGCACUCCAGCCUGGGCGACAGAGCAAGACUCUGUCUCAAAAAAAAAAAAAAAAAAAAAGUUUCUCCCAGCAAAGGCUAACUGGAAUUUAUUUUUGUUUAAAGACAAAUACUUUUAAUGUGGAUAAAAUAAAAGUUGGAAGUAUGCCUUUCAUGUGGCAAACUGGAAAUUAGUGGUUAGUACUCCAUUGCAGCAUUAAAUACCAAUUCUUUACAAUAGGGUGCACAUAUCAGAUGCUGUUUUUCCCUUAACCUUUGCACUUUUCAUUGAAAAUGUUUUCAAAUCAAAUCUUGUUUUAUUGGGUUUCACAUGAUUGGACUAAUACUUACAUAUAUGCUUCUUUUUAAGGUAUUUAGACAUUGACAAUUAGUUAUUUCCUUAUGAGCCAUAGCUUUGAAAAACCAUUUUAGAAGAAAUUUCCAUUUUUUAAACAAAAGUGUUGGGAGGCCGAGGCGGGCAGAUCACGAGGUCGAGACCAUCCUGGCUAACAUGGUGAAACCCCGUCUCUAAUAAAAAUACAAAAAAUUAGCCAGGCAUGGUGGUGGGCACCUGUAGUCCCAGGUACUUGGGAGGCUGAGGCAGGAGAAUGGCGUGAACCCGGGAAGCAGAACUUGCAGUGAGCCAAGAUCGCACCACACCACUGCACUCCAGCCUGGGCGACAGAGCGAGACUCCGUCUUAAAAAAAAAAAAAAAAAAAAAAAAGUGAUUUUUUAAAGAAAAGAUACCGAUAAUUUGUCUUUGCUGUAGAUGAAUGCCACGUUUUUAUAUACUAGGACUAUUACUGAAUAAUACUGUUUAUUUCUUUAGAUCAACGAAUAUAUUAAAUUCUGUCUUUUUUGUUCAAAUAAACGCUGUGAGAUGAUUGGGAAGGCUGUGUGUUGAAGUUAGAUGCAAAGUUGGACCUUGUACAGUGAGCCUCUUGUGAGAACUGAGCCAUGAAAGAUAAAGCCUGUCAUUCAUGUCUGCCUUGGCCUGUGCCCAGCUUUAUUAGUAAAAACCAUUCAGUUUUUACUAAUGAUAUCUACCAGUAUCUAAAGAGAAAUACCUUCAUCCUCUAGAAGAAAACAAGGUUACCCAAAGAGCUCACUUAAUUCCUUCCUUUUUCCCUGAACCCUUGGUUUUAAGUGAAGAGUAAAAUGUACUAGAUAUGACACUCUCUCUGAGUAUUACUGAGGAUUUUGUGGAAAAGGCAGUUUGGUACUUUAUUUCCAGCUUAGCUGCAGACUUGGUGACCCUGAGCAAAUCACUCAGCCUCCCUUUGCCUCCAUUUCUUCAUCUGUAAAAUGGGGUUAACCUGUGCCUCCCUGUCUCACCAGCAUACUGAGGGAUCGAUUAAAGAGGAUUAAAAAAAUCCAUAAGGUACACUGAUUCCAAAGAUGGGUAGAAUGAUAUUUAAUAAUGAAGACUUUCUGUUAUAUAGCAAUUUAAUUUUAAAAGUAUCUUUACCAGGCCAGGUGCGGUGGCUCACUCCUGUAAUCCCAGCACUUUGGGAGGCUGAGGAGGGUGGAUCACGAGGUCAGGAGAUCAAGACCAUCCUGGCUAACACGGUGAAACCCCGUCUCUACUAAAAGUACAAAAAAAUUAGCCAGGCAUGGUGAUGAGCGCCUGUAGUCCCAGCUACUCACGAGGCUGAGGCAGGAGAAUGGCAUGAACCCGGGAGGCGGAGCUUGCAGUGAGCCGAGAUCACGCCACUGCACUCCAGCCUGGGGGGCAGAGUGAGACUCUGUCUCAAAAAAAAAAUAAAAUAAAAGUAUCUUUACCCACUUCUCUGUAGUGAAUAUUGACUAGCAUUUUGAAGUAGGAACUAACAAAGUAUAAAAUUAAGUAGAUUUUUUAUAUUUAUGGGUAUUGUUCUAGUACAAAUUUAUGGUGUACACUGUCGGUCUGAGUGUGGGUUUAAAAUAUAUCAUUGUGCUUGGCUAAUUUGUAGAAUGUCUUAUUUGAAUUGACUUCAUUUAUUUCAGAGGAAUGCAUAGAUGAUCAGAUCAAACUGUCGUCAUAGCAGUGUUUUCAGCACAUACGAGAAUCUUAGAGUUUAGGAGCCUUAGAGCUCACCCAGUGCAAUUUCCUGCCGGAAGCAGAUUCCUUCCUGGUGACCUCACCAACAGGUGCUUGUGCAGCCUUUUCCUGAAAACUUUUUGGGAAAGUGGGGGCUGCUACCUCACUACUUUGAUGUGUACCUUUUGUUCAAGAACUUUCUAAAACUUGGAGCUAAUCAUGGGUUAUUUCAGAAGAUGUAAGCAUUUUAAGUUUUUUAUUGAAUUCCAUCCUUAUUUAAAAGGCCUGGUUAUGUAAUAUUUUCUGUUUUUUUUUUUUUUUUUUGUAUGGUUUCCCACAUUGAUUAGGUUGUUUUCUUCAUUUUCUUAAUAGAUUAAAAAUACUUUCUUCUCUUUCUAUUUGUGUCUUCUUCCAUUUAGUAUUUAUGGGAGGGAGCAAGAAGGGAAAGGAUGUCUAUUUUUAAAAUUGACUACAAUCAUGACUGUUCUUCUUGUCAUUCUGUAGCAGCUGGAUUUAUUACCAUCUCUUAUUUAAAGGUCCUUCAGAACACGUUGAAGCAGUUCAUUUCAGGUCAAUGGCUGGUAAGCAAUGUCAGGACCUCUGGGGAAGGAGAAGCUGACGGGAUCCCAGAGGAAAGAAUUGAGGUUGUUUGCUCCCUUGUAGAAAGCCCACAGAUCCCUUCCCAGACUAGAAAAAAAGUGCCAGAGUGUCCUGAAACUUUCCUUCUAAGGCACAUACUUCAAAGAGACUGGGGAUUCCUUUGUUUUAAAUAUAGGUGGGGUCUCACAGUGUUGCCCAGGCUGGGCUCAAGCGAUCCUGCCACCUGGGCCUCCCAAAGUGAUGGGAUUACAGGCAUGAGCCACCAUGCACGGCCAUGGAGAUUCUAAUGUGGUGCCAGCUGCCAGGUAAGAAAGCUGUGAGACAAUGUGUUGAUUUUCCUUUACUACGUCAGGUUUGAGGACAUCAUCUAGCAUCAACGGGUAACGUCACCCUUUGUUCCAUCUUUGGGAAAUAAUAGUAGUAGCUUGUUACUGUUAGCUGACCCCUACAUUAGCAUCAAUAAAGUAAAUCCCUUUAACUUUCCUUUUGGCCUUUCCUUUCUCUCUCUCUGCCUCCCCACCAGCCCCGACUCUCUCCUGUGUGCGUACACAUCCACACACACCUCCAUGGUAUUCCUUCUUUCUCCCACCUAAGGGAAGCUGUGCCCGAUCUUGCUGCAGUCCAGGUCACCGUACUGAGAUGAGUCAGCCACAGACUCUAAACACUAGCAGCGAUUAGCCGUAUGUAGCCACCAAGUGCACUGUUUUAGACAGGUUUACACAGCUCUUUGCUGUCCACUCAUAUCAGCUGUGUAGUAGCCCAAGGCAGCCUGUCAGGCAGAAGAAUUACCAACCAAAGUGGAUCUAUUCAUAAGAUAAAAGAUCCGGAGUCCGUGCCCUCUUAAAAAACUUUUGUCUUCAGACAUAUGGGUGCGUGUUCAUCUCUGGCCAAAACUUUGUUUCCAGUUUCAAAGGGCUGGUUGCGAAGGUGGCCUUGUAACCUUUCUGUUGCCGGCUCUGUUAGUUGCCUGAUAAGCAGUAGCUAAUUCAUCCUCCUCAGAAUUUGAGAGUGGCAUCUAUUAGAUUCAGACCACCAAGGUGCCUGCGCGGGCUCUCCUGGUUACGACUGAGUCCCCUUUUCUCAUCUGUGGGGUGAACGCUUCUAUUUGCAGAAAUUUGCUUGCAUCUUUUUCCUUUUAUUUAUUAUUACUUUUUAGAGAUGCGGCCUUGCUCUGUUGCCCAGGCUGGAGUGCGGUGGACUCUUUUCUUUUGUUGAUCUUUGCCAUCCUCUGCCUGGCUUAAUGAGGUUCUUUCCCUGCGUAUUUAUGUCCCAGGAGCUCACCUUCCCCCUAGGUUUUUAAGAAGGAAGCAGAAAAUGUUACAAAGUAUAAGGGAUUCUAUGAAGUCCAUAGAUAGGAUUUGCUUUGGGAGUAGAUGAUUUCUUCUUAUUUUGGUGUAAACAUCAAUUUGGAUGGCAAUUAGAAUGUCUUUAGCCUCUUUAAAAAGCCCUUCUGGGGCAAACCUUUGCAAGUCACUCAGCUGGCAUGUAAUGAGAUUUUUAUUUGCAUGGCUUUUUUUUUCUAAGUCUCUCUAGAAGAACAUAAGGACAUUCUGAACAUGCAAGGAAUACAGUUAUUCUCACAUCAAGGAUCAAUUUUAUUUUGUAUCUUCAUUUUAUGUCAUUUUCCUUUAUUUUAUUCACAUUAAUCUAGCAUUAAUUCCCCCCAGAGGGAAUGAUAUUUUUGGUUGCUGCCACCUGUGUUAUUAAGUGACAGCUUUUCUUUAUCUGCUUUUCUGAAUUUCAUAUUUAUAUACUUUAUUGUAGUUUUUUAAAAUCUAUUCUAGCUGGGCUAGAAUCUUCCAAGUAUUAAUUCAUAAUGAACUUCCCUCUUCUGGAAUUGUUUAGGAGGGCUAAUGUUCCAUGUUCCCUUCGUUGCUAUAGAUAUGAAGUUAUUUCGAUGUUCUUUGAGUGCUUUAUUAUAGCGAUAACUGGUACUGCCUUUGAUUAAAGGUGAGCUAUAUGGAGUUAAGCAUUUUUAUACUAGUAACUAUUUAUUGAGAAUUUUCAGAAUUCUAUAGCUACUUGUCUUUAACAGUUAUAAGAGGCAUGUAUUUUUUUUUCCUUCAUGGUCUGGAAGUUAGUUUUCUCUUUGUUUGGGUAGAUCGGAAUGAGUUGUUGAGCUGUGUUGAAAACACACAUGAAUCAAAAAAGCAGAUGUAUUGUAGAAAUGUGAUGUUUUCAUGUUUCGGGAAUUUGACCGGAAAGCUUUAUGUAUGGGUUUUAUUUUUAACAAAGCAGUAAGGGCUUACUUUUUACCAACUUGUGUGUGUGUAAAGAUGUAUUUGUUCAAGCUUUAAGAAUAAACCUGUCAAUGUACAAAUGCCUGA